AACCGUCCCGGCCACCGCUGCCUCAGCCUCUGCCUCCCAGCCUCUUUCUGAGGGAAAGGACAAGAUGAAGUGGAAGGCGCUUUUCACCGCGGCCAUCCUGCAGGCACAGUUGCCGAUUACAGGCCGGCCUCUCAGCCCUCAAUGAAAGAAAGCUAAUUGUAGAGUCAAGAAUAUGACCUGCUAUAAUGGUUCGAUCCUGGGAGAAGGGACUCCACAGCCUGGUGAGGACCCCUCUCACCACCUCUGAGGAUCAGCAAGUCUUUGAAGAGGCACAGAGCUUUGGCCUGCUGGAUCCCAAACUCUGCUACCUGCUGGAUGGAAUCCUCUUCAUCUAUGGUGUCAUUCUCACUGCCUUGUUCCUGAGAGUGAAGUUCAGCAGGAGCGCAGACGCCCCCGCGUACCAGCAGGGCCAGAACCAGCUCUAUAACGAGCUCAAUCUAGGACGAAGAGAGGAGUACGAUGUUUUGGACAAGAGACGUGGCCGGGACCCUGAGAUGGGGGGAAAGCCGCAGAGAAGGAAGAACCCUCAGGAAGGCCUGUACAAUGAACUGCAGAAAGAUAAGAUGGCGGAGGCCUACAGUGAGAUUGGGAUGAAAGGCGAGCGCCGGAGGGGCAAGGGGCACGAUGGCCUUUACCAGGGUCUCAGUACAGCCACCAAGGACACCUACGACGCCCUUCACAUGCAGGCCCUGCCCCCUCGCUAACAGCCAGGGGAUUUCACCACUCAAAGGCCAGACCUGCAGACGCCCAGAUUAUGAGACACAGGAUGAAGCAUUUACAACCCGGUUCACUCUUCUCAGCCACUGAAGUAUUCCCCUUUAUGUACAGGAUGCUUUGGUUAUAUUUAGCUCCAAACCUUCACACACAGACUGUUGUCCCUGCACUCUUUAAGGGAGUGUACUCCCAGGGCUUACGGCCCUGGCCUUGGGCCCUCUGGUUUGCCGGUGGUGCAGGUAGACCUGUCUCCUGGCGGUUCCUCGUUCUCCCUGGGAGGCGGGCGCACUGCCUCUCACAGCUGAGUUGUUGAGUCUGUUUUGUAAAGUCCCCAGAGAAAGCGCAGAUGCUAGCACAUGCCCUAAUGUCUGUAUCACUCUGUGUCUGAGUGGCUUCACUCCUGCUGUAAAUUUGGCUUCUGUUGUCACCUUCACCUCCUUUCAAGGUAACUGUACUGGGCCAUGUUGUGCCUCCCUGGUGAGAGGGCCGGGCAGAGGGGCAGAUGGAAAGGAGCCUAGGCCAGGUGCAACCAGGGAGCUGCAGGGGCAUGGGAAGGUGGGCGGGCAGGGGAGGGUCAGCCAGGGCCUGCGAGGGCAGCGGGAGCCUCCCUGCCUCAGGCCUCUGUGCCGCACCAUUGAACUGUACCAUGUGCUACAGGGGCCAGAAGAUGAACAGACUGACCUUGAUGAGCUGUGCACAAAGUGGCAUAAAAAACAUGUGGUUACACAGUGUGAAUAAAGUGCUGCGGAGCAAGAGGAGGCCGUUGAUUCACUUCACGCUUUCAGCGAAUGACAAAAUCAUCUUUGUGAAGGCCUCGCAGGAAGACCCAACACAUGGGACCUAUAACUGCCCAGCGGACAGUGGCAGGACAGGAAAAACCCGUCAAUGUACUAGGAUACUGCUGCGUCAUUACAGGGCACAGGCCAUGGAUGGAAAACGCUCUCUACUCUGCUUUUUUUCUACUGUUUUAAUUUAUACUGGCAUGCUAAAGCCUUCCUAUUUUGCAUAAUAAAUGCUUCAGUGAAAAUGCA